ACCUGACCAAGACCCUGGAGUUACAAUGGCGGCGCCCAUGCUGCGCUGGGGCUGCCGUGGAAGACGUUGGGCUUUCGCCCGGGUUGACGGUGGUUCUUGCCACCGAAGAGGGGCUCCGACUGGGUCCACAUCCAACCAGAUUAGGGGAGAGAGCUCAGUGGCUCAGCAGCCCCUCCACACGGCCCAGAAGACGAGGAAAGGUGAACACAAAUGGGCUGCUGUGGUAGGUUUGGAAAUUCAUGCCCAGAUUUCCUCCAACUCUAAACUCUUCUCUGGAUCUCAAGUUCGCUUUUCAGCACCUCCAAAUUCUUUGGUUUCUUUUUUUGAUGCAUCUCUACCUGGAACUUUGCCGGUUCUCAACAGGAGGUGUGUAGAAGCGGCGGUGAUGACAGGCCUGGCUCUGAACUGCCACAUAAACAAGAAGUCCUUGUUUGACAGGAAGCACUACUUCUAUGCAGACCUCCCUGCAGGCUACCAAAUUACCCAGCAGAGGCUCCCAAUUGCUGUGAAUGGGAGCUUGAUAUAUGGCGUCUGUGCAGGGAAGAAGCAGAGUCAGGUGAUCCCCAAGACGGUGAGGAUCAAGCAGAUCCAGUUGGAGCAAGACAGUGGCAAAAGCCUCCACGACAACCUGAGGUCUCAGACGCUCAUUGAUUUGAACAGGGCAGGAGUGGGCCUUCUGGAGGUGGUCCUGGAGCCCGACAUGUCCUGUGGAGAAGAGGCGGCAACAGCUGUCAGGGAGCUGCAGCUGAUCCUUCAAGCCCUGGGGACCAGCCAGGCGAACAUGGCAGAGGGCCAGUUGAGAGUGGAUGCCAAUAUAUCCGUGCAUCACCCUGGGGAGCCUUUGGGCGUUCGAACGGAAGUGAAGAAUCUCAACAGCAUCAGGUUCCUGGCCAAAGCCAUAGACUAUGAAAUUCAGAGGCAAAUCAAUGAACUUGAGAAUGGAGGUGAAAUUCUGAACGAAACACGCUCAUUUCAUCACAAGCUGGGGUGCACCAUGUCAAUGAGAGACAAAGAAGGAAAACAGGACUACAGGUUCAUGCCAGAACCCAACCUGCCUCCCCUGGUGCUCUACGACGCCACAUCUCUGCCCGCAGGUGCAGACCCACAGCAAGUGAUCAAUAUUGACCAGAUUCGGGAGACACUCCCGGAGCUCCCCAGUGUGACCCGAGAGAAGCUUGUCCAACAGUAUGGGAUGCUGCUGGAACACAGCUUCACUUUGCUGAACGAAGUCGGCCUACUGGAGUUCUUCCAAAAUGUGAUAAAAGAAACUAGGGCAGAGCCAAAAAAGGUGACUAGUUGGGUCCUCAACACUUUUCUGGGCUAUUUAAAGCAACAGAACCUCGCUGUCAGUGAGAGUCCUGUCACACCCUCUGCACUCGCUGAGCUUCUUGACCUGCUGGACAGCAGAACAAUUUCUUCAUCAGCAGCUAAACAGGUGUUUGAGGAACUGUGGAAGAGGGAAGGCAAGACUCCAGGGCAGAUUGUUUCAGAAAAGCAGCUUGAACUGAUGCAGGACCAGGGGGCACUGGAGCAGCUCUGCCACUCUGUGAUGGAGGCCCAUCCUCAAGUGGUAAUGGAUGUGAAGAACAGAAACCCCAGAGCUAUAAAUAAACUGAUUGGGUUGGUCCGGAAAGCGACUCAAAGCCGAGCAGAUCCAGUCAUGAUAAAGGAGAUCCUGGAGAAGAAGCUGUCAUUGUGAGAUGUUUGGGAUCCCCUUGCCCAAGGGACAACAACAAACAGUGCAGCCUGACUGGGAACAGGAUCCUGUGAAAGCUGAUGCCCAUGUGCCCUGAGAGCUGCCUCUCAAUCCCUGUCCCAAGCCACAGCUAUGGCAUUAAUGUCACCAGUGUUCUCACCCUCUAGGCCCUGUGCCUGGAGGUGCCUCCACAGCCGACCAGCAGCCACCCCGCCUGCUUCAUCCACAUCAGGAGGGUCCGGUGAGGCUGCAGCAGUGGUUAAGGAGUAACACCUUCUUGUAUUAAGGAAUUUUAAACUAAAUAAAAUGUAUGUUGGAGAUACUGUUACCCAUUCUAAGAAAACUUUUCAUUCUGCAGUUCCUUCAACAAAUAUUUUUGAGCAACUCCUAAGGGCCAGCCAUUGUAGGUGAUGGGCAUUAGCAGUGGUCAAGAGAGACUGUAAUUUGGAUGUAUUGUUUUCAGACCUAAACACAGGUUAACAAAGAUGAAAAUACAACCAAAUAAACUGGCACAGUAUAAACACAUUUGUUUGUUUAAGGAGGUCUCAAGAGGGUGGGGAAGGAGGAUAUUAUUAGAAUUAAUCAACCUAUCGACUGAGUAGAAGUGAUAUUGCCUGUUAAACUCCCUCCCCAUCCCAGAAGGCACAGUCUGAGAAUAAAUGAAUUAAAAAAA